AUUGGAGCUUCCCGGACCGUGUGCUCGACGGUGCCCUAGGUGCCGUGGGGCCACACGCGAGUCUGAUAAGCACCCUCCCCCGGAAUCAUGCGGUGCUGUGAGGCCUAGCGAAGAUGAAGAUAGAAUGCAAGGUAGAAAGUGCUGGAUACCUUUAGAAAGCUGCAGGACUGGUGCGAUGGGAGUUGAGACGUAAGAACCUGCCCGUCCGUAGGGCUCUGGAUGCUGCUGAGGCCCGAGGCCCCUAUGGCAGAUUUGAAAAUUCACCCUUGUAGAGUCAUUCCUGCCUUUGAGCGGACUCCCUUUUAAGUUUACAGAAGCACUUGCAGAACUCAUCAGAAGCCACCCCGCUUAUCAGCAGAUCUCAAGAGAGCGUUCGGUGGAGGCCCUGGGUCUGCACAGCUCACCUCCCUGGGAACUGCUCGCCCGAGCGUCGGAGCCGGCGCUGGCCCCCUGCAGCCGGAAGGUUGCAGCCGCAGGAGCCCCGGAGGCCCAGGACACAGGACAGAGUCUCGUUCUGUCGCCCAGGCUGGAGUGCAGUGGUGUGAUCUCGGCUCACUUCAACCUCCGCCUACAGGGUUCAAGGGAUUCUCCUGCCUCAGCCUCCUGAGUAUCUGGGUACCCACCAUCAUGCCUAACUAAUUUUUUAAUUUUUGUAUUUUUAGUAGAGACAGGGUUUCACCAUGUUAGCCAGGCUGGUCUCAAACUCCUGGCCUCAAGCGAUCCACCUGCCUCCACCUCUGCCUCCCAAAGUGCUGGGAUUACAGGCAUGACCACUGUACCUGGUCACUAUAUUUUCUUUAUGUAUGAUUUGCAUAUUAUUACUUUUUAAAUAUUUGAUGACUGAUAUUGGAAUGAGGAUCAGGGAGGAAAAUAAUAAAAUCCAAGAUUUCUGUAUUACCGUGCCGGGUAGGUUUUCAAUAUCAUGACCAUAUAGCCCUGUCACUUUCAUGUCGGUGAAACAAAGUAGUCAGGACUUUUAAAAUUUUCAAAUGAUUUAAUAUAUGCCUGAUACCUACCCUCCUUUCCUUCCUUCUUUUUUUUUUUUUUAAGAGACAGGGUCUCACUUGGUCACCCAGGCUAGAGUGCAGCGGUGCAAUCAUAGCUCAUUGGAAUCUCAAACUCCUGAGCCCAAACUCCUGCCUCAGCCUCCCAAGUAGCUGGGACUACAAAUACGCACCACCAUGCCUGGCUCAUUUAUUUUAUUUUUUGUGGAGAUGGCAUUUCACUAUGUUGCCCAGGCUUAUCUUGAACUCCUGGGCUCAAGCAGUCCUCCCUCCUCGGCCUCCCGAAGUGCUGGGAUUACAGGUGUGAGUCCCCAUGCCCGGCCUUUUUUUUUUUUUUUGAGACUCGCUCUGUCACCCAGGCUGAAGUGCAGUGGCACGAUCUCAGCUCACUGCAAGCUCUGCCUCCUGGGUUCAUGCCAUUCUCCUGCCUCAGCCUCCCGAGUAGCUGGGACUACAGGUGCCCAGUAGCAUGCCUGGCUAAAUUUUUUUUGUAUUUUUGGUAGAGACGUGGUUUCGCCAUGUUAGCCAGGAUGGUCCUGAUCUGACCUCGUGAUCCGCCCGCCUUAGCCUCCCAAAGUGCUGGGAUUACAGGUGUGAGCCAUCAUGCCCGCCCAAGUCUGCUUCCUUGUCUCUGCAUUUAGUUCUCCUAAGAGAUUCUCUUUCCCUCUCCCUUGUCUUUGUACCCUGCUAAUCAGGUGUACAUGAUUUCCUAUCAGACUUGAACCUUGCAGAAUUGAAGCCAUAGAAGAGUAUGUUGACUCUACAGUGCUUGAAGGCUCUUGCUCUUGCAGAAUCCACAGGUCUUUCUUGAGGAAAUCUGUAGACAGAACUUUGUGCUGCGUUUUUAUCUAGGGAAGGAACAGAAGAGUGUCGUCUCCUAGAAAUCUAGCACUGGAGAAACGAGGAAAAUUCUUCCAGCGAUGGUCUCCCACUCAGAGCUGAGGAAGCUUUUCUACUCAGCAGAUGCUGUGUGUUUUGAUGUUGACAGCACGGUCAUCAGAGAAGAAGGAAUCGAUGAGCUAGCCAAAAUCUGUGGCGUUGAGGACGCGGUGUCAGAAAUGACACGGCGAGCCAUGGGCGGGGCAGUGCCUUUCAAAGCUGCUCUCACAGAGCGCUUAGCCCUCAUCCAGCCCUCCAGGGAGCAGGUGCAGAGACUCAUAGCAGAGCAACCCCCACACCUGACCCCCGGCAUAAGGGAGCUGGUAAGUCGCCUACAGGAGCGAAAUGUUCAGGUUUUCCUAAUAUCUGGUGGCUUUAGGAGUAUUGUAGAGCAUGUUGCUUCAAAGCUCAAUAUCCCAGCAACCAAUGUAUUUGCCAAUAGGCUGAAAUUCUACUUUAACGGUGAAUAUGCAGGUUUUGAUGAGACGCAGCCAACAGCUGAAUCUGGUGGAAAAGGAAAAGUGAUUAAACUUUUAAAGGAAAAAUUUCAUUUUAAGAAAAUAAUCAUGAUUGGAGAUGGUGCCACAGAUAUGGAAGCCUGUCCUCCUGCUGAUGCUUUCAUUGGAUUUGGAGGAAAUGUGAUCAGGCAACAAGUCAAGGAUAACGCCAAAUGGUAUAUCACUGAUUUUGUAGAGCUGCUGGGAGAACUGGAAGAAUAACAUCCAUUGUCGUACAGCUCCAAACAACUUCAGAUGAAUUUUUACAAGUUAUACAGAUUGAUACUGUUUGCUUACAGUUGCCUAUUACAACUUGCUAUAGAAAGUUGGUACAAAUGAUCUGUACUUUAAACUACAGUUAGGAAUCCUAGAAGAUUGCUUUUUUUUUUUUUUUAACUGUAGUUCCAGUAUUAUAUGAUGACUAUUGAUUUCCUGGAGAGGUUUUUUUUUUUUUUGAGACAGAAUCUUGCUCUGUUGCCCAGGCUGGAGUGCAGUGGCGCGGUCUCGGCUCACUGCAAGCUCUGCCUCCCAGGUUCACGCCAUUCUCCUGCCUCAGCCUCCCGAGUAGCUGGGACUACAGGCACCCGCCACCACAUCCGGCUAAUUUUUUGUAUUUUUAGUAGAGACGGGGUUUGACCGUGUUAGCCAGGAUGGUCUUGAUCUCCUGACCUUGUGAUCCGCCUGCCUCAGCCUCCCAAAGUGCUGGGAUUACAGGCUUGGGCCACCGCGCCCAGCCAAUGUCCUAGAGAGUUUUGUGAUCUGAAUUCUUUAUGUAUAUUUGUAGCUAUAUUUCAUACAAAGUGCUUUAAGUGUGGAGAGUCAAUUAAACACCUUUACUCUUAGAAAUACGGAUUCGGCAGCCUUCAGUGAAUAUUGGUUUCUCUUUGGUAUGUCAAUAAAAGUUUAUCCGUAUGUCAGAA